CCAGCCCCUGUGAAAUUUUAAAAGGAAUGGUUGCAGCUUUUUCUUGCCCUUUGGUUCCCUGUAGUGAACACAUGUUGCCAAAAGAUGGCAGUGCACUUUGCAGCCACUGAGAUCGCUCUUCCCUGUCGCCUGGGGCUUAGAGAAUUGUGUCUUGUUCUUUAUGUGUAUGUUGAAAAUGUGCAGAGCAGAUUUUACAAAACAACAAAAGCACCAAUAAAAUGCUGUGAAGUUUAGAAUCAUGAAAAAAAAAUCACGUUUGCAAAUGGUUUAUAAUGGAAAUAGUCCCCCACUUCUUAAACAUGAUUUGAAUAGGGAAUAGAACUCAGAAAUGUGUGUAUGAGUGUAUAAUUUUAGGUGUCAGUACUGAUUGUUAUAUUCUGUAUAGCUCCUGAAAAAGACCUGUGAAAUGCUGAUUUUUGUCUUUCAUCUGAUCCAAGAUUAGCCAAGUAACAGGCCUGCUUUUGAACUCUGAGACUGCAGUCCUCAAGUAAAGGCCCUUGUAUACACUUAGUUUUCAUGGCAAAAAUGGCUAAUAAUAAAACUCUUCACUUGCUAGCAUUGGUCACUCCCCUGUGUGCGUCACUUUGGUGUGCGUCUGUGGGCAUGUGUGUAAAGAACUGUUUAAACAUUGGCUAUGCACCAGAAAGCUGUGUGAAGUGAGAGAUUAUGGGGUUCACCGGAUGUCAUAAACAGACCAAGCUGGUGAGGAUAAAGUGGGAUGAGUUGAAAUACAAGAUUAGCUAAUAAACUUUAAGCUGCAUGCACGGAGAGAACCAGUGAUAUUAAACUCUGGUAUGGGCAUGUUAAACACUGGUGCCCUGCUGCUCUCUAGGGUGCCAUCCCCGAUGCCUUUUGGGAUGGAAUCAAAAAGCCCUGCUAUGAACUUGAUCCAUGUGCAGCAUCGUUAAGUGCAGAGCAGGCUGUGGAAGAGAGUGGGCUAGCUCUGGGAUUGGGUAUACAAGCUCCGGAGUGGAUCCUCUACACACCAGCCAGUGUGUCAAGGUUGGAGGCUCUGUUUCACUUCCCCUGAGCUCAGUACCGCAGUCGCUUUCAUCCUACAGUUUACAAAGUAGCUGCAAUCCUGGGUGGCAGGGAAACAGGUGGCUUCACGGUAAAGCAGCAGGCUUUUUGCUACUGCAUCCUUUGGCAAAAGCUUGGGCUAGGAGGAGAAAUGUGCUGUGUAAAGUUUUAACCCUGAAAGCAGAUGCUGUUACUAUAGAGACAAGUGAAAUGCUACAGUGGGAGGCGUAACAGGGGAGGGAUGGGAGAAGGGAGGUGGGAGGGCAAGUAAGGCGAAUCUAAAGGCUAGCACACUCCAAGACCUUCAACCUUUAGCAGCACUGUGACGGGGCAGGCUUGCAUUCUGAAACUUGUGUGCUGGCGGCCUGCCACGUGCUGACUGGCUGAGUGGCAGCUGCUUGCGCUGUGCGGACUAGCUGGAUGGAGGAUGAAGCUGUCCUGGACAGAGGGGCUUCCUUCCUCAAGCAUGUGUGUGAUGAAGAAGAAGUAGAAGGCCACCAUACCAUUUACAUCGGAGUCCAUGUGCCGAAGAGUUACAGGAGAAGGAGACGUCACAAGAGAAAGACAGGGCACAAAGAAAAGAAGGAAAAGGAGAGAAUCUCUGAGAACUACUCUGACAAAUCAGAUAUUGAAAAUGCUGAUGAAUCCAGCAGCAGCAUCCUAAAACCUCUCAUCUCUCCUGCUGCAGAACGCAUCCGAUUCAUCUUGGGAGAGGAGGAUGACAGCCCAGCUCCCCCUCAGCUCUUCACGGAACUGGAUGAGCUGCUGGCCGUGGAUGGGCAGGAGAUGGAGUGGAAGGAAACAGCCAGGUGGAUCAAGUUUGAAGAAAAAGUGGAACAGGGUGGGGAAAGAUGGAGCAAGCCCCAUGUGGCCACAUUGUCCCUUCAUAGUUUAUUUGAGCUGAGGACAUGUAUGGAGAAAGGAUCCAUCAUGCUUGAUCGGGAGGCUUCUUCUCUCCCACAGUUGGUGGAGAUGAUUGUUGACCAUCAGAUUGAGACAGGCCUAUUGAAACCUGAACUUAAGGAUAAGGUGACCUAUACUUUGCUCCGGAAGCACCGGCAUCAAACCAAGAAAUCCAACCUUCGGUCCCUGGCUGACAUUGGGAAGACAGUCUCCAGUGCAAGUAGGAUGUUUACCAACCCUGAUAAUGGUAGCCCAGCCAUGACCCAUAGGAAUCUGACUUCCUCCAGUCUGAAUGACAUUUCUGAUAAACCGGAGAAGGACCAGCUGAAGAAUAAGUUCAUGAAAAAAUUGCCACGUGAUGCAGAAGCUUCCAACGUGCUUGUUGGGGAGGUUGACUUUUUGGAUACUCCUUUCAUUGCCUUUGUUAGGCUACAGCAGGCUGUCAUGCUGGGUGCCCUGACUGAAGUUCCUGUGCCCACAAGGUUCUUGUUCAUUCUCUUAGGUCCUAAGGGGAAAGCCAAGUCCUACCACGAGAUUGGCAGAGCCAUUGCCACCCUGAUGUCUGAUGAGGUGUUCCAUGACAUUGCUUAUAAAGCAAAAGACAGGCACGACCUGAUUGCUGGUAUUGAUGAGUUCCUAGAUGAAGUCAUCGUCCUUCCACCUGGGGAAUGGGAUCCAGCAAUUAGGAUAGAGCCUCCUAAGAGUCUUCCAUCCUCUGACAAAAGAAAGAAUAUGUACUCAGGUGGAGAGAAUGUUCAGAUGAAUGGGGAUACGCCCCAUGAUGGAGGUCACGGAGGAGGAGGACAUGGGGAUUGUGAAGAAUUGCAGCGAACUGGACGGUUCUGUGGUGGACUAAUUAAAGACAUAAAGAGGAAAGCGCCAUUUUUUGCCAGUGAUUUUUAUGAUGCUUUAAAUAUUCAAGCUCUUUCGGCAAUUCUCUUCAUUUAUCUGGCAACUGUAACUAAUGCUAUCACUUUUGGAGGACUGCUUGGGGAUGCCACUGACAACAUGCAGGGCGUGUUGGAGAGUUUCCUGGGCACUGCUGUCUCUGGAGCCAUCUUUUGCCUUUUUGCUGGUCAACCACUCACUAUUCUGAGCAGCACCGGACCUGUCCUAGUUUUUGAGAGGCUUCUAUUUAAUUUCAGCAAGGACAAUAAUUUUGACUAUUUGGAGUUUCGCCUUUGGAUUGGCCUGUGGUCCGCCUUCCUAUGUCUCAUUUUGGUAGCCACUGAUGCCAGCUUCUUGGUUCAAUACUUCACACGUUUCACGGAGGAGGGCUUUUCCUCUCUGAUUAGCUUCAUCUUUAUCUAUGAUGCUUUCAAGAAGAUGAUCAAGCUUGCAGAUUACUACCCCAUCAACUCCAACUUCAAAGUGGGCUACAACACUCUCUUUUCCUGUACCUGUGUGCCACCUGACCCAGCUAAUAUCUCAAUAUCUAAUGACACCACACUGGCCCCAGAGUAUUUGCCAACUAUGUCUUCUACUGACAUGUACCAUAAUACUACCUUUGACUGGGCAUUUUUGUCGAAGAAGGAGUGUUCAAAAUACGGAGGAAACCUCGUCGGGAACAACUGUAAUUUUGUUCCUGAUAUCACACUCAUGUCUUUUAUCCUCUUCUUGGGAACCUACACCUCUUCCAUGGCUCUGAAAAAAUUCAAAACUAGUCCUUAUUUUCCAACCACAGCAAGAAAACUGAUCAGUGAUUUUGCCAUUAUCUUGUCCAUUCUCAUCUUUUGUGUAAUAGAUGCCCUAGUAGGCGUGGACACCCCAAAACUAAUUGUGCCAAGUGAGUUCAAGCCAACAAGUCCAAACCGAGGUUGGUUCGUUCCACCGUUUGGAGAAAACCCCUGGUGGGUGUGCCUUGCUGCUGCUAUCCCGGCUUUGUUGGUCACUAUACUGAUUUUCAUGGACCAACAAAUUACAGCUGUGAUUGUAAACAGGAAAGAACAUAAACUCAAGAAAGGAGCAGGGUAUCACUUGGAUCUCUUUUGGGUGGCCAUCCUCAUGGUUAUAUGCUCCCUCAUGGCUCUUCCGUGGUAUGUAGCUGCUACGGUCAUCUCCAUUGCUCACAUCGACAGUUUGAAGAUGGAGACAGAGACUUCUGCACCUGGAGAACAACCAAAGUUUCUAGGAGUGAGGGAACAAAGAGUCACUGGAACCCUUGUGUUUAUUCUGACUGGUCUGUCAGUCUUUAUGGCUCCCAUCUUGAAGUUUAUACCCAUGCCUGUACUCUAUGGUGUGUUCCUGUAUAUGGGAGUAGCAUCCCUUAAUGGUGUGCAGUUCAUGGAUCGUCUGAAGCUGCUUCUGAUGCCUCUGAAGCAUCAGCCUGACUUCAUCUACCUGCGUCAUGUUCCUCUGCGCAGAGUCCACCUGUUCACUUUCCUGCAGGUGUUGUGUCUGGCCCUGCUUUGGAUCCUCAAGUCAACGGUGGCUGCUAUCAUUUUUCCAGUAAUGAUCUUGGCACUUGUAGCUGUCAGAAAAGGCAUGGACUACCUCUUCUCCCAGCACGACCUCAGCUUCCUGGAUGAUGUCAUUCCAGAAAAGGACAAGAAAAAGAAGGAGGAUGAGAAGAAAAAGAAAAAGAAGAAGGGAAGUCUGGACAGUGACAAUGAUGAUUCUGACUGCCCAUACUCAGAAAAAGUUCCAAGUAUUAAAAUUCCAAUGGACAUCAUGGAACAGCAACCUUUCCUAAGCGAUAGCAAACCUUCUGACAGAGAAAGAUCACCAACAUUCCUUGAACGCCACACAUCAUGCUGAUAAAAUUCCUUUCCUUCAGUCACUCGGUAUGCCAAGUCCUCCUAGAACUCCAGUAAAAGUUGUGCCUCAAAUUAGAAUAGAACUUGAACCUGAAGACAAUGAUUAUUUCUGGAGGAGCAAGGGAACAGAAACUACAUUGUAACCUGUUUGUCUUUCUUAAAACUGACAUUUGUUGUUAAUGUCAUUUGUUUUUGUUUGGCUGUUUGUUUAUUUUUUAACUUUUAUUUCGUCUCAGUUUUUGGUCACAGGCCAAAUAAUACAGCGCUCUCUCUGCUUCUCUCUUGCAUAGACACAAUCAAGACAAUAGUGCACCGUUCCUUAAAAACAGCAUCUGAGGAAUCCCCCUUUUGUUCUUAAACUUUCAGAUGUGUCCUUUGAUAACCAAAUUCUGUCACUCAAGACACAGACACGCACAGACCCUGUCCUUUGCCUCUAUUAAGCAGAGGAUGGAAGUAUUAAGGAUUUUGUAACACCUUUUAUGAAAAUGUUGAAGGAACUUAAAACUUUAGCUUUGGAGCUGUGCUUACUGGCUUGUCUUUGUCUGGUAGAACAAACCUUGACCUCCAGACAGAGUCCCUUCUCACUUAUAGAGCUCUCCAGGACUGGAAAAAGUGCUGCUAUUUUAACUUGCUCUUGCUUGUAAAUCCUAAUCUUAGAGUUAUCAAAAGAAGAAAAAACUGAAGGUACUUUACUCCCUAUAGAGAAACCAUUGCCAUCAUUGUAGCAAGUGCUGGAAUGUCCCUUUUUUCCUAUGCAACUUUUUUUAACCCUUUAAUGAACUUAUCUGUUGAGUACAUUGAAGAAUAUUUUUCUUCCUAGAUUUUGUUGUUUAAAUUAUGGGGCCUAACCUGCCACUUAUUUUUUGUCAAUUUUUAAAACUUUUUUUUAAUUACUGUAAAGAAAAUGAAUUUUUUCCUGCAGCAGGAAACAUAGUUUUGAGUAGUUCUACCUCUUAUUUGUAGCUGCCAGGCUUUCUGUAAAAAUUGUAUUGUAUAUAAUGUGAUUUUUACACAUACAUACACACACAAAUACACAAUCUCUAGGGUAAGCCAGAAGGCAAGAUCAGAUUAAAAACACCAUGUUUCUAAGCAUCCAUUUUUCCCUUUCUUUAAAAGAAACUUAACUGUUCUAUGAAGGAGAUUGAGGGAGAAGAGACAAACUCCUAUGUCAUGAGAAUAACCGAUGUUCUGAUAAUAGUAGCAUCUAGGUACAGAUGCUGGUUGUAUUACCACGUCAAUGUCCUAUGCAGUAUUGUUAGACAUUUUCUCAUUUUGAAAUAUUUGUGUGUUUGUGUAUGUGCUCUGUGCCAUGGCUGGUGUAUAUAUGUGCAAUGUUAGAAGGCAAAAGAGUGAUGGUAGGCAGAGGGCAAAGUCAUUGAAUCUCUUAUGCCAGUUUUCAUAAAACCCAAACCACAUAUGAAAAAAUCCAUUAAGGGUCCAAGAAGUCUGUCCAUAUGAAAAUGAGGGUAAAUAUAGUUUAUUUCCCAGGUAUCAGUCAUUAUAAUUGAUAUAAUAGCUCUAACAUGCAAUAUAAAAUUCAUAGGAGUAUUAAUAGCCCAUUUACACAUCUAUAAAAUGUAAUGGGAUUGCAGAGCUGCAGAGUACAGUGUAACAGUACUCUCAUGCAAUUUUUUUCAGGAUGCAAAGGCAAUUAUUCUUUGUAAGCGGGACAUUUAGAAUAUAUUUGUGUACAUAUUAUAUGUAUGUAUAUUUCAAAGUACCACACUGAAAAUUAGACAUUUAUUAACCAAAUUUAACGUGGUAUUUAAAGGUAAUAUUUUUAAUAUGAUACAUUACAUAUUGUGAAUGUAUACUAAAAAAACAUUUUAAAUGUUAAAAUUAUAAUUUCAGAUUCAUAUAACCACAACUGUGAUAUAUCCUAACUAUAACCAGUUGUUGAGGGGUAUACUAGAAGCAGAAUGAAACCACAUUUUUUGGUUUGAUAAUAUGCACUUAUUGACUCCCACUCAUUGUUAUGUUAAUUAAGUUAUUAUUCUGUCUCCUUGUAAUUUUGAUUACAAAAAUUUUAUUAUCCUGAGUUAGCUGUUACUUUUACAGUACCUGAUACUCCUAAAACUUUUAACUUAUACAAAUUAGUCAAUAAUGACCCCAAUUUUUUCAUUAAAAUAAUAGUGGUGAAUUAUAUGUUAUUGUGUUAAAACCUCACUUGCCAAAUUCUGGCUUCACAUUUGUAUUUAGGGCUAUCCUUAAAAUGAUGAGUCUAUAUUAUCUAGCUUUCUAUUACCCUAAUAUAAACUGGUAUAAGAAGACUUUCCUUUUUUCUUUAUGCAUGGAAGCAUCAAUAAAUUGUUUAAAAACCAUGUAUAGUAAAUUCAGCUUAACCCGUGAUCUUCUUAAGUUAAAGGUACUUUUGUUUUAUAAAAGCUCUAGAUAAAACUUUCUUUUCUGAUCAUGAAUCAAGUAUCUGUGGUUUCAUGCCCCUCUCUAUACCUUUCAAAGAACUCCUGAAGCAACUUAACUCAUCAUUUCAGCCUCUGAGUAGAGGUAAAACCUAUGUGUACUUCUGUUUAUGAUCCAUAUUGAUAUUUAUGACAUGAACACAGAAUAGUACCUUACAUUUGCUAAACAGACAGUUAAUAUCAAAUCCUUUCAAUAUUCUGGGAACCCAGGGAAGUUUUUAAAAAUGUCAUUACUUUCAAAGGAACAGAAGUAGUUAACCAAACUAACAAGCAAAACCUGAGGUUUACCUAGUGACACCAAAUUAUCGGUAUUUUAACUGAAUUUACCCAUUGACUAAGAAUGAACCAGAUUUGGUGGUGGUUUUGUUUCUAUGCAAACUGGACACAAAUUACAACAGUAAAUUUUUUUAUAAGUGCUUCUCCCUUCUCCAUGAUGUGACUUCCGGAGAUAAAGGAUUCAAAAGAUAAAGACAAAGUACGCUCAGAGUUGUUAACCAGAAAGUCCUGGCUGUGGUUGCAGAAACACUGUUGGAAGAAAAGAGAUGACUAAGUCAAGUGUCUGCCUUAUCAAAAGAGCAAAAAUGCCUCUGGUUUUGUGUUUGGGAGAAAAGUAUCUUGGACGCACUGUUUUCCUUGAUAAAAGUCAUCUUCUCUACUGUGUGAAAUGAAUACUUGGAAUUCUAAUUGUUUUGUGUGCCAGGGGCAGUAAUGUCCCUGCCUCUUCUCCCAAUCAAGGUUGAGGAGUGGGGCUGGGGAGAGGACUUAACUGACUUAAGAAGUAGGAAAACAAAAACCUCUCUCCUCAGCCUUCCACCUCCAAGAGAGGAGGAAAAACAGUUGUCUGCUGUCUGUAAUUCAGUUUGCGUGUAUUUUAUGCUCAUGCACCAACCCAUACAGAGUAAAUCUUUUAUCAACUGUAUACUGGUGUUUAAUAGAGAAUGAUUGUCUUCCGAGUUUUUUGGUUCCUUUUUUAACUGUGUUAAAGUACUUGAAAUGUAUUGACUGCUGACUAUAUUUUAAAAACAAAAUGAAAUAAUUUGAGUUGUAUUACAGAGGUUGACAUUGUUCAGGGAUGGGACAAAGCCUUCUUCAAUCCUUUUCAUACUACUUAAUGAUUUUGGUGCAGGAACCUGAGAUUUUCUGAUUUAUAUUUCAUGAUAUUUCACAUUUGCUCUUCACAGCAUGAGCAUGAAGCCCAGUGGCACCAAAUGGCUGGGUACAAUCAAGUGAUAUUUUGUAGCACCUCACUAUCUGAAAGGCCAUGAGUUUUCAGAUGAUUUCAUUGAGCUUCAUUGCAGCCUGAAAUUUUAAAAAAGUUGUGUAAUACGCCAACCAGUCAAGUUGUGUUUUGGCCAGAGAUUUAGAUAUGUCCAAUUUCCUGGCUCAUUUCAUUGUGCUCUAUGGGUACGUAUAAAAAGCAAGAAUUCUGUUUCCUAGGCAAACAUUGCAACUCAGGGCUAAAGUCAUCCAGUGAAACUUUUAGAGCCAGAAGUAACUUUGUCCCAGUCCUACAAUGUGAAAAGAGUGAAUAGUUGCCUCUUUUUAGCCAUUUUCAUGGCUGGUACAUAUUCGUACGCAUUACUUUUCAGAAUCAAUACGCACUUUCAGAUAUUCUUAUUUUUAUUCUCUUAAGUCUUUAUUAACUUUGGAGAGAGAAAUGAUGCAUCUUUUUAUUUUAAAUGAAGUAGAUCAACAUGGUGGAACAAAAUGAUAAAGAACAGAAAACAUUUCAAUAUAUUACUAAUAACUUUUUCCAAUAUAAAUCCUAAAAUUCCUAUAACAUAGUAUUUUACAGUUUUAUGAAGCUUUCUAUUGUGACUUUUAUGGAAUUAAGAGAUGAAGAAGAUGAGAUAUUUUAGCAUUUAUAUUUUUCAAAAUUAUAUGUAUACUUAAAAAUAAAGUAACUUUAUGCA